GAACACCGCGGGGCAAGAUGGCGGUAGUGCGUCGGCUGCUGCCCCGGGUCUGGCAGAACUCGGGUGUUUUGGGCUGAGACAGUGGCAGCUGCGGCCCCGACCCCAAGUGCGGGGACCUCCGGCGAAUAAAGGUCGGCCUGCGGGUAGGCCGGUAGGGCCUGCGGUCCGGCCUGCGGGAGAACUGGGUCGUCAGUCCUCCGAGUGGUGGGGCUGGGGACUUUGAGGGAGUUGGCUCUAGGGCACAGUCCCUGCCUGGCCAGGUCGGAGGAACAAGUGCUGGGAUCUGGCGUGUGUGCUCCAGGGGCUCUUUCCGCGGCCCUUUCCACCUCUUUUCACUUUGGGGACGGUAGGCCUUUAUAAACGGACUAAUGCUGGGUGAUUUGUUCCUGUGGUUGUUGAUGCCGAGGAAAGACUCUGGGCCCCAGGACUCACCUAAACUGGAGUUCGAAUACUGUUCGCUCGCUGUGUGACCUUGGAAAAAAUAACAAGCUUUUCUGAAGUGAGAAGCUGUUCUCAGCCACGAGUCCUGUGCAAGAUCACUAAUGAUUACCUGGCAUUUCUGCGACACAGGCAGGUCCUCAGGGUUUGUGCAAGUUUGCAAACAUGUUCACCCUGUCUCAGACCUCGAGAGCAUGGUUCAUCGAUAGAGCCCGUCAGGCACGAGAAGAAAGGCUUGUGCAGAAGGAACGGGAGCGGGCAGCUGUUGUGAUCCAGGCCCAUGUCCGGAGUUUUCUCUGUCGGAGUCGACUGCAGAGAGAUAUCAGGAGAGAGAUUGAUGACUUUUUUAAAGCAGAUGACCCUGAGUCCACUAAAAGAAGUGCACUUUGUAUUUUCAAGAUUGCCAGGAAACUGCUGUUCCUAUUCAGAAUCAAAGAGGAUAAUGAGAGAUUUGAGAAGUUGUGUCGCAGCAUCCUGAGCAGCAUGGAUGCUGAGAAUGAGCCUAAGGUGUGGUAUGUGUCCCUGGCUUGUUCUAAGGACCUCACCCUCCUUUGGAUUCAACAGAUCAAGAACAUUUUGUGGUACUGCUGUGAUUUUCUCAAGCAGCUCAAGCCUGAAAUCCUGCAGGACUCCCGACUCAUCACCCUGUACCUCACGAUGCUUGUCACCUUCACAGACACUUCAACGUGGAAAAUUCUUCGGGGAAAAGGUGAAAGUCUUCGACCAGCGAUGAACCACAUUUGUGCAAAUAUAAUGGGACAUCUCAACCAGCAUGGAUUUUAUUCUGUGCUGCAGAUAUUGUUAACCCGUGGCCUGGCAAGACCCCGUCCUUGUCUAUCCAAAGGCACUUUAACAGCAGCUUUUUCUCUAGCGUUACGCCCUGUGAUUGCUGCACAGUUCUCAGACAAUCUGAUUCGGCCGUUCCUCAUCCACAUCAUGUCUGUGCCUGCUCUGGUGACUCAUCUCAGCACAGUGACCCCUGAGCGCCUCACUGUUUUAGAAUCCCAUGACAUGCUUCGUAAAUUCAUCAUAUUUUUAAGAGACCAAGAUCGAUGCCGUGAUGUAUGUGAAAGUUUAGAAGGAUGCCAUACGCUUUGUCUAAUGGGCAACCUCCUACACUUGGGCUCCCUCAGCCCCAGAGUGUUAGAGGAGGAGACAGAUGGGUUCGUGAGUUUGCUCACCCAGACGCUGUGCUACUGUCGGAAGUAUGUGUCUCAGAAGAAGUCCAACCUGACCCACUGGCAUCCUGUCCUUGGCUGGUUCUCCCAAUCUGUGGAUUAUGGCCUUAACGAGUCAAUGCACUUGAUCACCAAACAGCUGCAGUUCUUGUGGGGGGUGCCUCUGAUCCGGAUCUUCUUCUGUGACAUCCUGAGCAAGAAGCUACUGGAGAGCCAGGAGCCAGCCCACGCACAGCCAGCAUCCCCUCAGAAUGUGCUCCCAGUGAAGAGUCUCCUAAAGCGUGCUUUUCAAAAGUCGGCAUCAGUCCGGAAUAUUCUCAGGCCUGUCGGGGGUAAACGGGUCGACUCUGCAGAAGUCCAGAAGGUUUGCAACAUCUGUGUCCUCUACCAGACCUCGCUGACAACUCUCACACAGAUUCGGCUGCAGAUACUCACAGGUCUCACUUACCUUGAUGACCUGCUUCCCAAACUGUGGGCAUUUAUCUGUGAGCUCGGGCCCCACGGAGGGUUAAAGCUCUUCUUGGAAUGCCUGAACAAUGACACUGAAGAGUCCAAGCAACUCUUGGCCAUGCUGAUGCUGUUCUGUGACUGUUCGCGGCACCUCAUCACAAUCCUUGAUGACAUUGAAGUUUAUGAAGAACAGAUUUCAUUCAAACUGGAAGAGCUGGUCACUAUCUCCUCUUUCCUGAAUUCUUUUGUGUUUAAGAUGAUCUGGGAUGGAAUUGUAGAGAACGCCAAGGGUGAGACCUUGGAGCUGUUCCAGUCUGUCCACGGGUGGCUUAUGGUGCUGUACGAGCGGGACUGCCGGCGGCGCUUCACCCCCGAGGACCACUGGCUGCGAAAGGAUCUCAAACCUAGCGUGCUCUUCCAAGAACUCGACAGGGACAGAAAACGGGCACAGUUGAUCCUGCAGUACAUCCCACAUGUCAUCCCUCACAAAAACAGAGUUCUACUGUUUCGAACCAUGGUUACCAAGGAGAAGGAGAAACUGGGGCUGGUGGAAACCAGCUCUGCCUCCCCGCAUGUCACUCACAUCACCAUCCGCCGGUCCAGGAUGCUGGAGGACGGCUACGAGCAGCUUAGGCAGCUCUCCCAGCACGCCAUGAAGGGGGUCAUCCGUGUGAAGUUUGUCAAUGACCUCGGGGUGGACGAAGCAGGGAUUGAUCAAGACGGUGUUUUUAAGGAGUUCUUGGAAGAGAUCAUCAAGAGAGUUUUUGACCCAGCACUCAAUCUGUUCAAGACAACCAGUGGGGAUGAGAGGCUGUACCCCUCACCCACAUCCUACAUCCAUGAGAAUUACCUGCAGCUCUUCGAGUUUGUGGGGAAGAUGCUGGGGAAGGCUGUGUAUGAGGGAAUUGUGGUGGACGUGCCAUUUGCAUCCUUCUUCCUGAGCCAACUGCUUGGGCACCACCACAGCGUCUUCUAUAGCUCGGUGGAUGAACUGCCUUCUCUGGACUCCGAGUUCUAUAAAAACCUCACCUCCAUCAAGCGCUAUGAUGGGGACAUCACUGACCUGGGCCUGACGCUGUCUUACGACGAGGACGUCAUGGGUCAGCUUGUUUGCCAUGAACUGAUUCCUGGAGGGAAGACCAUUCCUGUUACAAAUGAAAAUAAAAUUAGCUACAUCCAUCUGAUGGCACAUUUUCGAAUGCACACUCAAAUAAAAAACCAAACAGCUGCCCUCAUUAGCGGAUUCCGUUCCAUUAUCAAACCCGAGUGGAUCCGAAUGUUCUCAACUCCUGAACUGCAGCGUCUCAUCUCUGGCGACAAUGCUGAGAUUGAUCUGGAAGAUUUAAAGAAGCACACAGUCUACUACGGUGGUUUCCAUGGAAGUCACAGAGUCAUCAUCUGGCUCUGGGAUAUUCUGGCCUCCGACUUCACACCGGAUGAGAGAGCUAUGUUUCUGAAGUUCGUGACCAGCUGCUCCAGACCCCCGCUCCUGGGAUUCGCCUACCUCAAGCCUCCAUUCUCCAUCCGCUGCGUGGAGGUGUCGGACGAUCAGGAGCCACACUUUAAGAAGGAUGCAGGAGGCUGGGCGUGGUGGCUCACGCCUGUAAUCCCAACACUUUCGGAGGCAGAUGGAUGACUUGAAGUCAGGAGUUCGAGACCAGCCUGGCCAACAUGGCGAAACCUCGUCUCUACUAAAAACACAAAAAUUAGCCCGGCAUGGUGGCAGGCACCUGUAGUCUCAGCUACUCUGGAGGCUGAGGCAGGAGAAUCACUUGAACCCGGGCGGCAGAAGGUUGCAGUGAGCUGAGAUUGCGCCACUGCACUCCAGCCUGGGUGACAGAGCUAGAUUGUCUAAUAAAAAAAAAAAGUGGGGGGUAGCAGGAAAAACUAGCCCACAGCCAGAGAUGGUACCAUAAGGAGGGUUGGAGCGGGCCUCUCAAAGCAAGCCUAGCAGUGUACCCAAGCUACAUGUAGACGAUGGGCCACCCGAGAUGUUAGCAGCAUCCUGAGGGGGUGUCGGCCUCUGUCUUGGAGGGUGCUGGCUUAAGGGUUGAGCCUCAGACUGCAGGGUGUGUUUGGGAAGCAGCUGCCCACAGCUCUGGUCAUUAAAGAAGAGAGCGAGCUGGUUCUUCUGGCCCCAGCAAUAACAACAAAACAACCUGGAGUAUGGUCCCUGCAGCCCUUCCCAGACACAGAGUUCUCAUUCUCCAAACGUGGACAUCCGGAGGGACACACGGCCUUACGUGGCCACCAGCAGGCCAUGGACGGACAUUGCCCAGCCCACGUUGCUGCCACAGGUGGACACUCAGAGCGAGAGAGAGGGAAGUUGGGGUGCUGGUGGGAAUGGGUGUGGACUGGAAUGUUCUAGAGGUAUGGGGGGCCUGAGACAUCUUGUGAAGUGGGGCGGGGGGCGGGGCUUCUCCAUGAGGCCAAAGGUGAGCAGGCCUCUGGGUGUUUCAGAAGAACUGCCCUGGCAACAUGCAAGUACAGUUCUAGCAGAGACGCCAAAUCAACUGUCAAAACCGAGCCACUGCCACCCCACAAAGCCAGGAAAAGCUUCUAACUGACAAUCUUGGGUAAGUCGGCCCUCAGCCUCUGCAUCUCCCACCACAGACCAAGGCUCCCAGAUCCCCCCAGCCCAUGCACUCCAUGUGGUCCCCUCUGUGUGCCUGGAUACAUCGGGACUCUUGGGUGUCACUGGGGAUUCCUGCCCUGCCACAUGGGGUAAGCUACUGGUAAUUACUCAGCUGUGGGAGCUCCUGGUCAUCAGCCUUCAAACACAGAAACUCAGGUAUUUUUCCCAGCAGACCCUGACCAGCCUCUGUAUUUCUCCAUAACGCUGGUCGGCUGGGCACAGCGAUCUUGGCAACAGAUUUUGCGAAAUAAACUUGGUCAGUGGAUCCCAGUCAACAAAAUGUUUUUCCAUCUGUUACCCACUUCCUCCUGCCUGUGAAGGGGCAGUGCUCUCUCCUUCUUAUAGGUGAGGCUCUGAGAGGUGGAGUGAGUGACUUGCCCAGGGACUCAAAGCCAGGAUAUGAGGAACUGGGAUGUAAGCCCAAGCCUUUGACCAGGAAGGUGACCUCACUCACUCACUUGCCUUCCCUGAUCGUCAGAGGCCUGGACAGAAGCCUUCUGUCUCCCAGAGGGGCUAGUCCCACUGACUCUCCUGACCUGCUCCCAUCCCACUAGGGACACUGUCCAGGGGAGGGAGCACACCCCAUGUGGGGCUUGGUGUGAAGUCUGCUGGGUGGCUUUGUCACAUUGCAGAUGGUGCCAGAUGAGCCGGGCCCCGCCCAGGAAGCCAGACUGCCAGGGAGUUCAGACUCAGCCAACAAACAGACCCACAGGGCCUCCUGUGCCCCAGGCUGGGUGCUGAGUUACAGCCGUGCACACGGUGGACGUGAUCCCUGCCCUACAGAGCUCACUCUCUGGUGGGAAAGAGUCAGAACUAAUUCAAGGAGGAGGUGUAUGGCCACAUCCUGUGAUCAGCGUCCCUGGCAUCUAGUGCUGUGCUAUUCUGAUGCCCACUCAAGUGGGGAAAGCUGAGGUCAGGAGCUGGUCAUUCCCAUGCCCAAGGCCCCAGAGUCAGUUAAGUGGCAGAGCCAGGAUUCAAACCCUGGUCUGCCACACUCCAGAGCCCUCACUCGGUUUGAGCAGGCAGAAGAGGGGUGGGAGAACAUUCUAGGCAAAGGGCUCAGCUUGAGCCAAGCCCCAGGGGCUGCUCUGUCCCUUAUCUGGAGCCCGCUGCCUCCACUGCUUGUCCCACUUACCCUUGCCGGGGAUGCUGCAAACUGACAGACACACCCAUUUUGCCAGUGAGUUCCCACAGCAUUUUAAAGGACUUCUUCAGGACCCUAGAGCCCUGGUCUCCCCAAGGCUGCAGAGCAGCAGCUGCCCCCCAGGCACAGAGCUGAAAGGCAGAGCUGGAUUUCAGGGUGUGCUGAGUAAAGGGCCGAUCUACCCUGCACUUUGGAAGCUCACCGGGUAGAGGGAGGCCAGAGGAAUUUCAGGGACUCCACGACUUCCUUAGCUUAUCAUUCAUGUCCCAACAGGCUGCAGCCUGUCUCCCUACCAGCUAAGGCAGAGUUGCAAGUGGGACAGAAUCAGUGCCCACUCCAAACAUGGCUCCUUGGCUGCAUCUGGGAACGGGUUCCAUUAGGUGGUGUGUGGAGGGUCUCAAACAUCUUAACAGUGAUGGUGAAUGCGCCAGUGCCUCUGCAGCAGGGGCCAGAGUUCCUGUCUCCCCUCCUGGUUUGCUAUCACAGGGGCCCCUGGUGAAUAGGCUGGGUGGCUCAUCCCAGCGAGUGUUCAAACUCAAAAGCUGGAUGGCUAGAAACUGCCCACCUGCACCAAACCACCAUCAGAAGUGGUCUUUAUCAGCCAGGGCAACAGAAGCCAGCUCUGCCUCACUUAGAAAAGAAAUGUAUUGGGCAGUAUUGAGGGCUGGAAGCCCAGGCCACAAGCAGAAUGGGAGCCAGGGCAGUUCAGGGGACCUGUGCAGUUCAGCCUGAAGCUGGGUCUCUUUAGGAUGCUGUGGGCGUGAAUGAACCAGCUCCAGCCAGCAACCCAUCCUCGCUCAGUGCAUGCAGGGGUCUUUAGGGAAAUUCAGAGAAAAUUCAGGGAUUGAAGUAGACUGGGCAAGGCACUGAUGUCAUUCAUUCUUUCAUACUCAUUUCAAUAAAUAUUUUUGGGCACCUGCUGUGUGCACAGCCUGUUCUAGGCACUGGGAUUCAAUCUCAUUUUGUUGUUCUUGAGACUGAGUCUCAUUCUGUUGCCCAGGCUGGCAAUGUGGCACGAUCUCGGCUCGCUGCAACUUCUGCCUCCUGGGCUCAGGUGAUCCUCCCACCUCAGCCUCCCGAGUGGCUGGAACUACAGGUGCACGCCACCACACCUGGCUAAUUUUUGUAUUUUUUGUAAAGACAGAGUUUUGCAAUGUUGCUCAGGCUGGUGUUGAACUCCUGGGCUCAAGCGAUCCUCCUGCCUCAGCCUCCCAAACUGCUGGGAUUACAGGUGUGAGACACCACACCCAGCCGGAUUCAGAGUAUUUUGAGAGAGACAGACACCAAAGGAGAAACCAAUAAGAUAAUUUCUGGUGUGUUGAAAAUGAGACAAAGAGCCCCAUGGAGAUUGUAUCCCAUGGGAAGAAGUAAAUCCUCAAAAAGAAAUUGAAGCAAUUGGAUGGUGGGUCCCCAAACAGCAAAUAUCCACAAGAGGCGUCCUGCCCACACUGGCCCCAGGGCAGUGAUCAGGAUUCAGAUUCCAGAACUAGACUAGAAUUCAAAUCUAGCCUCAGCCACUUUCUCAUCACGACCUGGAGCAAGUCACUUCGUCUUUCCAAGCUUGCAAAAUUGGGAUGAUCACUCUUCCCUGGUUGCUGAGAUCAAACAAGGUCAUACAUGCAGUGCCGGCCAUGCAGGCAUCAUCGAGUUCCAUCCUGAGAACUCGAUCACGUCCUGGGUGCAUGUGCGCGUACGCGCGCACACACAUGUACACACGCACACGCAUGCAUGCAUGCACGGUGGGGCACCCAAGCCGAUGCCCGCUCCUCGAGGCUGGGGGCUAUGCAUGCCUGACCCUCUGGUGUAUUCAAUUAUAGGUUUAGCCACAUUCAUUCCUCCCUCCUUGUAGGUAAGAUUUAUUAAAAUACCCAAUCACAGAAAUAGCCCUGCUCCCUGACAGCAGCCAACCCACAGCGAAACCACGUUUCCUUGAACCCUCCCCCAAACCCCAACACACGCCAAAACCCUAUAAUAAGUCCUUGCACAGACCCUCUUCCUGAGGCACCCCAGGUUCCCCACGGUGCGCGUGCUCCCUUAUUGCAACAAGACAAUAAAUCUGACUUUGUUCGACUA